GGCGUCGAGCACCGCCUUAUCCAGCCGCACUGGGGGCUUCGUCCCCUGCGGGGUGAGGGGUCUCCCCUGUGUCACCCUCCGAGGCCACGCUAGACGUUGUGGCGCUCAGGGCUCCCGGUUCCUGCCGCGCUGGGGCUCCCCCGUCCCAGCCUCCCUCCCCACCUCUCCCAGGCUCCCCUCCCCUGUCGCAGCCACCCUCCCCCGUCCCAACCUCCUCCCCUUCUCUCGCACGAUCCGGCCAAGAGAUGGCGGGGUGGCGGGAGGGGCGCUCUGGCGACCCCGGAAGCGAGAAGCAGGCCUCUGCAGGGCCAGGGAUGAAGGUGCAAGGGAAAGCCCUGGGACCUGGACCUUAGGCGUGGGAGGGACGAAAGGGAAAGGUCUUAGAAAAUUCCUCAGGCGUGGCUUCUGGGGGGGCGGGGCGGGGGGAGGAAAGGGGCACGGGUUCCCGGUCUCGUAGACGCUGCAGCGGAGCAGAGCCUCUAGGCAUGCCCUCAUCUAGAGCAGCUGCUGCGGAAUCCGGGGAGCCUGCAGCACUAGCCGUGCGAUUCCGGGCGAGGUUUUUAAACUCUCACCUGUUUUCCCCUUUUGUAAACUGAAGAUAAUGCCUCUCUCCCGGGAGUGGGAGCACGAUGCUGACACACCGUAGGAACUCGGGACUUGCUGAUUCUCCUUCCUUAUCCUCAAGGCGUUUGAAGCACUCCUGCCCCUCACCCCCACCCCUCCAGCCCCUUUCCCAGCCCUGCCCCCUGGUGGAAAAUCCUAAGAGCUACCUCUCAGGAGGGCUCCUGUAAACCAGGCACUGUACACACACCUUUCAUUUCAUCUUCGCAGCAGCUCUUUUUGCAUCCCAGCUAUGGCUGGCGAUUCUAGGAAUGCCAUGAACCAGGACAUGGAGAUUGGAGUCACUCCCUGGGACCCCAAGAAGAUUCCAAAACAGGCCCGCGAUUAUGUCCCCAUUGCCACAGACCGUACGCGCCUGCUGGCCGAGGGCAAGAAGCCACGCCAGCGCUACAUGGAGAAGAGUGGCAAGUGCAACGUGCACCACGGCAACGUCCAGGAGACCUACCGGUACCUGAGUGACCUCUUCACCACCCUGGUGGACCUCAAGUGGCGCUUCAACUUGCUCGUCUUCACCAUGGUUUACACUGUCACCUGGCUGUUCUUCGGCUUCAUUUGGUGGCUCAUUGCUUAUAUCCGGGGUGACCUGGACCAUGUUGGCGACCAAGAGUGGAUUCCUUGUGUUGAAAACCUCAGUGGCUUCGUGUCCGCUUUCCUGUUCUCCAUUGAGACCGAAACAACCAUUGGGUAUGGCUUCCGAGUCAUCACAGAGAAGUGUCCAGAGGGGAUUAUACUCCUCUUGGUCCAGGCCAUCCUGGGCUCCAUCGUCAAUGCCUUCAUGGUGGGGUGCAUGUUUGUCAAGAUCAGCCAGCCCAAGAAGAGAGCGGAGACCCUCAUGUUUUCCAACAACGCAGUCAUCUCCAUGCGGGACGAGAAGCUGUGCCUCAUGUUCCGGGUGGGCGACCUCCGCAACUCCCACAUCGUGGAGGCCUCCAUCCGGGCCAAGCUCAUCAAGUCCCGGCAGACCAAAGAGGGGGAGUUCAUCCCCCUGAACCAGACAGACAUCAACGUGGGCUUUGACACGGGCGACGACCGCCUCUUCCUUGUGUCUCCUCUGAUCAUCUCCCAUGAGAUCAACCAGAAGAGCCCUUUCUGGGAGAUGUCUCAGGCUCAGCUGCAUCAGGAAGAGUUUGAAGUUGUGGUCAUUCUAGAAGGGAUGGUGGAAGCCACAGGCAUGACCUGCCAAGCCCGGAGCUCCUACAUGGAUACAGAGGUGCUCUGGGGCCACCGAUUCACACCAGUCCUCACCUUGGAAAAGGGCUUCUAUGAGGUGGACUACAACACCUUCCAUGAUACCUAUGAGACCAACACACCCAGCUGCUGUGCCAAGGAGCUGGCAGAAAUGAAGAGGGAAGGCCGGCUCCUCCAGUACCUCCCCAGCCCCCCACUGCUGGGGGGCUGUGCUGAGGCAGGGCUGGAUGCAGAGGCUGAGCAGAAUGAAGAAGAUGAGCCCAAGGGGCUGGGUGGGUCCAGGGAGGCCAGGGGCUCGGUGUGAGGGGUGCAGCCUCCCUAAGACCUCCUGUCACUGGCUUCAGUGAACACAGACACUGCAGAGCCUGGGAGCAGGGGAGGGGAAUAGUUGAGUGUGCUGUUUGGGGGCUCAGGAGCCAUCAAGGCUGUGGGGAGGAACCAUAAACCCAGCCCUCACAGCUCCCAGCACAGGGCCUCCCUGAGCCAGUGGCAUCCUGCCUGGGCCCCCCAUGGCAGUGCUGCCUCUUGUAGGUGCUGGCUAAGGGCCAGGCCAGGAUGAGUUUCCCCAUGGUGAAUGUUACCGGAUGGCAUCUGUUCUCUCCAUGCCCUGGGUCACUUCCUUUUUUGGGUCUCACAGACCCCUCCAGGGGCUGACACCUAGAGAGAACCAUCACCUUGUCCCUCAUUCCUUCCACCCUGAGGCUUGCUGUGGACUCAGAGAGGAGACUUACCUGAUGAGAGCUCAAACCUCUAGUCUGGGAUGAGCUCACAGAGCCCUCAUGAGUUAAGAUCCAUCCAUAUCACAUAGGCAAUUCCUUUUAAAUCAGAUACCAACGACCCAUUACUGAGAGGUACAGAGCGUACAGCCCUUGGUGUUCUCUGCUGUUAUCUGCCAAAUGUGUGUGUUUUUCCUCUGCUGUGUUCUGUGUGUCCAGUGUAGCCUAUUGGAGAAUCGGUCUCAUUAGAGUGACUCUUAGAAGGUGGCCUGGGACUAGACAGCCCCUCUGAGCACAUGCAUAGUGGCAUCAGCAGCUUCCUGGCCUACUCCCAAUCACACUGUGCCCUGCACCUCCCACCAAGGGGGAACCCCAGCAGCUGGGGCUUUUCGAGUGCUUUUUGGCCCAAGAAUCUCAGAGUGCUUCUAAUCAUCACAGUAGUUUUUGUGUUUUGUUUUGUUUUGUUUUGUUUUGUUUUGUUUUGUUUUGUUUUUUUCACAAUCUCAGCCAGCCUGCGGUGUGACCUGGGGAGAAAGUUGAGUGUCAGGGGACAUGAUGAGCCAGUUGGCCCUGAAACAGGAAUGGGGCAAAGAGAAAGGAGAGCCAGGAGCAUUUAAAAAUCAGCAUCUGGGCCAGGCAAGAUGGCUCACGCCUGUGAUCCCAGCAUUUUGGGAGGCCGAGGCGGGUGGAUCAUGAGGUCAGGAGAUCGAGACCAUCCUGGCUAACACGGUGAAACCCCGUCUCUACUGAAAAUACAAAAAAUUAGCCAGGCAUGGUGGCAGGUGCCUGUAGUCCCAGCUACUCGGGAAGCUGAGGCAGAAGAAUGGCAUGAACCUGGGAGGUGGAGGUUGCAGUGAGCCAAGAUCAUGCCACUGCACUCCAGCCUGGGCGACAGAGCGAGACUCCAUCUCAAAAAAAAAAAAAACAUCAGCAUCUGCCCCAGUUGUGGCCAAGACACUCUGACCUCAGGGCUCAGCACCUUCACCAUCAAGUUCAGCCUGAGCCAAGCUCCCAGCCCACUGCUGAAAAGCCCCUGGGCCUCCCUCCACAGGCAGAGUUACAACCGGGAGGGCUGGGCAGGGAGGGCAGGGAGAUUGCCUGGGGAAGGCAAAGGGAAUGGCUGCCCCUCCCAGGCUGGAAACAAGAGGGCAAGCGGGGUCAGCAGGAGAAUUCGGGGGCAGGGUGAGUGUUAAGAAAAAAAGAGUAGAGAAGAGCCUGAAAAUCAGCAACUUCCAGGGCUUUUCUGAUCUGGAGGCCCAAGAGCAAGGGUGGAGGGGGGCAGAUUGUCAGGUCCCGAAAUGUGUGUUGACACACACGGGCUUCGGGUUAGCUGGCCUGACAUGGAGAUAGAGUGCCAAUGUUCCCAGGCCACAGAAUUAUGGAGGCCUCACCCACAGUAUUCACAGCUCUCAACUGGCCUUUGAGAAUGGAAGCCUUUUCCUGCCCUGGAUAUGGCGCUUCUUCCUGGGAGAGGAGCAGAGCCACAGAGAGGUAGGAAGUUGAGGCAGAGCAAAGGGAAGGCUUCAGAGCUUAGGCCCGGUUCAUCUCAGAAGUGUUUUCUAGGCCUGGGGCUGAAAGGAAGAGGGGUGGGGCAGCCUGGGACGGGAACUGCCUCUGUGGGCUCCCCACUCCCAGGGAGGGGCUCCAUAAGCUUUGCUCCUGGGCUGGAUCUUGAGAGGUGGGCAGGGUCUUCCCACCAGUGGCAGGGUGUGCAGUUGUGGUCCCAAGCCUUGGAGGGAAUGGGGAAUGGGCUGGCACCCGGCUCAGGGAAAGCAGAAGCAGACAGUGCCCCAGCAGGGGAGCUGCAUGCCCCCAGGAGUCUCAGAAAGGCAGCCCAUCACUAAGGCUGGAUGCCUUUCAGCAGAGCUACAGCUGGAGCCCUCCGGCUGAGGCCAGCACUCGCCUGGGACUCCCUGGACCCCAGGGUUACUAACAGCAAAACCAUUCCACACCCCCUUGCCAGAUCUAAGCCUGUCUUAGGACCGUCAGUGCCCCCAGGUUAGAGCUCAUGGGGGUCAACUAAGCGAGGGAGGGAAGGCGAAGGCAAAGCUGGCCUUGCACCUGGACAGCGGCCUGGCUCCUCCCCACACCUGCCUUCAUUUAUGACUCUGAAACAUCCCCCACCUGACCAAGGGAGCCACUCUCCAGUUCUCUCACUCCACCAGGGCCCUCCGUGAGCCAGGACCAGGUCACAUCUCUCAGCCAAGUCUAGAAGCUCUGGCUAGAGGAGAGGAAGCGUGCAGAGGGUCCUCUGCCAAAGCUCCCUGCCUGGCCCGAGCCCGGGCAUGCUGGGAUUAGUGCAACACCGCCCCAGUGUGCCUCCUCUGCCUUCUAUCAUGCCAGUUUAAAAGCAAGAAGACUCCCCCUUCACAUCCUGAGGAAAUCCCCUUCCUGGUGACCAACUGAUGCAAUGAAAGUUUGAAAAGUUCUUCAUUUUCUAGAAGUUCUUGAAUAAACAUGGACUUACUAAAUGCAGAGUCUGAUGAUGGACAGAGUUUCAAGGGGUCACUUUCAAAACAUUUAAUUAAUUUAUUUAUGUAGAGACAGGGUCUCGCUCUGUCGCCCAGGCUGGAGUGCAGUGGUACAACCUCAGCUCACUGCAACCUCUGCCACCUCCCAGGUUCAAGCGAUUCUCAUGCUUCAGCCUCCUGAGUAGCUGGGAUUACAGGCAUGAGCCACCACGCCCAGCCAUUUUCAAAACACUGCUCCUGCAUACAAACCACUCAGAGGCCACUGCCCUUGGUUCUGUGAUGGCUCUGAGCCCAUGCCAUCACAUCUGAUGGACCCCAGAGAGCUGAGCCGUGGUUUAAGAUGGGGUCAUGCGCUGGUCAUUCCCACAGUCUUGAGUAUCUCCAAAAUCCCAAAGUGAUAUUUCACUUUCGGACCCUGAAAGUUUGGAGAGCUGGUUUCUUGCCUUAAUUUAAGCUCUCUGAGAAUGUCCCCUGUAGGGAGAAGCCUCCAGGAACUCAGAAUAGAACUCGUUCCCACUCAUUUUCCUUGCUCCACCAAUCUGACGCCUGACAGAUGUCACCACUGCCUGAAGGAUCCUGUCCCCAGGCCAGGGCAGAAUGGGCAUUGCCUUUGACUCUCCCCUUCAGACUCCCCUCCCACCGGCCUCCUGUGUAGUCAGAGAACCCACUGCCCAUCGCCUCCUGCUGCUGCUUUGAGGUUGAGGUCCUGGCUUGAGCAGUUACCUUGCUGGAGAAGAGGAGCCCCUGCCAUCUGGGGAGCACUGUCCCUGCUCGUGAUCUGUAACAGUGGGGCGCUUUUUCACACCCCUUAUCUCACGGCUUGCUUCCAGCCCCCAUCAAUCCUGUGCCUCAUGUGAGGUGAGCCCCAGAGAAACUUAAAUUGCUUGUACUGAAGUUGCCAAAAACCAAAAGUUGCCCGUUGUCAUUUUUAAGACUGUGCCCUGAACACACCUCUGCCCAUGCGCCAUGGAGCAUGUGUUAGGUGCCUGCCGUGGGUCAGGCACUUGAUUCUCAAAACACUGCCGAGAAGCUCUUACCAACGUGACAGUUGAGGCUGAGAGAGGUUCAUGAGCUUGCUCAAGGCCACGGGUAGUAAUAAGAGGCAUGGCCUUGGUGCCAAGUGCCUCCCAAACAAACAGCCGGGGCCGUGGUCCUGCCUAAACUCUCACAUCCACGGCACCACGCUGGGCCCAGGCAACAGAGAUAAGGAGAGCCCUGGCUCUUGGGAUGGGGUCGCGCCGAUUCACAUGCUGUGCCACGGAGCCCCGGCUUCCAUCCAUGAUGUGCCCCUGUGGCGGGAUAAUUGGGAAACAACCUUUUUCUGAUUCCCAGAGAACUAAUGAGCUGCAAAAAGAGAUUAGACAGGGAAGAAUUGCUUUCGGGGAGAAGCCACUUACUCGGCUCGCCUUGGUUUUUGCUAACAACGUCUCCUUAAACUGCUGUCAAAUCUUUUUCUCCCUGUGUAGGAUUCAUCAAUCUUCGUAUGCAAAAGAACACCACUGCACUGCACUGCUAAAAAUUCACACAAUAAAAUGGACUUUAACUUGCA